CCCUGUGCGUCCCCCGCUGGGCCAGCUCUCAGGGGCAGGAGGGGGGUGCAGGAGGCAGAGAUGGCAGCAGCUGGGGCUGGUCUUCCGACUUCUCGCUAAAGGCAGAUCCAUCUGUGGGGAGGAUCUGGGCCGAGUGUGAACAUGGGGAGGAUCCGGGCCGAGUGUGGCCGUGGGGAGGGCGGAGAUGAGUCUGUUCUUCCUGAGCUGCUGGCUGGGGCUGUGGAACUUUGGCCGUGGUCUUGUUGGGUGCCUGUCCUAGAGCAGCCCCCAGGGGUGACGGAGACCACACUCUCUGUGGGGAUGGGAUUGGGGUGGCUUCUGAGGAGCAGGUGGCCUGGCCCUGAGCUGGUCCUUUCUGGGUACCCUGGUGCCCUUGCCCUCUAGCCGGUGGGGCCGUGCUCGCCUGUGGUCCUAGCCAGGUGGCCUGAAGCCUGGCCCCUUUUCCAUCUUCUGUGAAAUGGGGCUGUGGUUGAGAGCUGGGGGCCUGGCAGGGCUGGUCACAGCACAGGGACAUGCCGACUGCUGGGCUGGGCAGGGUGCGUGGCCGCCCCUGAAGUGUAGUUUUGGAGUAAGAAGGAAUGGAGUUCAGGAAUUCCCUCACAGCUCUGCCUGUGGCUCUGGGCUGCCCCCGCCAGUGUUGCACCCUGAGCCUGGCAAUCCACGGAGGCCUGGUGCAGGGGCUCAGGGCCGAGGGCAGAGCAGGCCGGGCAGAGCCGAGAGUGCCAUCCCUGUCCGCACACGCUGCCGUCGUAGUUGAGAGAGGCCCUCAGUGGGUGCGGGGCUCAAGGCGGCUUAGUGGGCAGGCAUGGGCUGUGACAAGUAUCACUCAGGACUUGUAUGUGCGGUUCGGGAGUCCCACGGCCGAGGGAGGGAUUAGUGGCGCUUUUAGGCCUGGGGCCCUGUUGUCAGGUGAAGAAGGCUUGAUGCCCUUCGGCCUCCCUGUUCUUGGGUCCUCCUGGGGGGCCGGAGGCUGUCAGCUGCAGAGGGGGAGCCAGCAGGCGCCCCCAGCCUGACCCGAGCCUCGAGUGAGGGUCCCAGGAGAGGAGGCGAAUGGGCACAGAGCUGGGGGCCCACCCACUGCUGCGGGUGAUGCCUGCCGCUCCCUCCUCUGGGCCCCCAGGUCCCCCCGGGGGGUAAUAAGACGCAGUAUGAUGAGAUUGGCAUUCCCGUGGCCCUGCUCAGCUACAAAGACAUGCUGGACAUCUUCACGGCAGCGUUUCGGCCGCACGGUGAGGGCGGCGCUGUAUGCGCCUAAGGAGCCGGUGCUGGACUACAACAUGGUCAUCAUCUUCAUCAUGGCUGUGGGCACCGUCGCCAUCGGCGGCUACUGGGCCGGGAGUCGGGACGUGAAGAAGUACAUGAAGCACAAGCGCGACGAUGGGCCCGAGAAGCAGGAGGACGAGGCGGUGGACGUGACGCCGGUGAUGACCUGCGUGUUUGUGGUGAUGUGCUGCUCCAUGCUGGUGCUGCUCUACUAUUUCUACGAUCUCCUCGUGUACGUGGUCAUCGGGAUCUUCUGCCUGGCCUCCGCCACCGGCCUCUACAGCUGCCUGGCGCCCUGUGUGCGGCGGCUGCCCUUCGGCAAGUGCAGGAUCCCCAACAACAGCCUGCCCUACUUCCACAAGCGCCCGCAGGCCCGUAUGCUGCUCCUGGCGCUCUUCUGCGUGGCCGUCAGCGUGGUGUGGGGCGUCUUCCGCAACGAGGACCAGUGGGCCUGGGUCCUCCAGGAUGCCCUGGGCAUCGCCUUCUGCCUCUACAUGCUGAAGACCAUCCGUCUGCCCACCUUCAAGGCCUGCACGCUGCUGCUGCUGGUGCUGUUCCUCUACGACAUCUUCUUCGUGUUCAUCACGCCCUUCCUGACCAAGAGUGGGAGCAGCAUCAUGGUGGAGGUGGCCACUGGGCCCUCGGACUCAGCCACCCGUGAGAAGCUGCCCAUGGUCCUGAAGGUGCCCAGGCUGAACUCCUCACCUCUGGCCCUGUGUGACCGGCCCUUCUCCCUCCUGGGUUUCGGAGACAUUUUGGUGCCAGGGCUGCUGGUGGCCUACUGCCACAGGUUUGACAUCCAGGUACAGUCCUCCAGGGUAUACUUCGUGGCCUGCACCAUCGCCUAUGGCGUUGGCCUCCUUGUGACAUUCGUGGCACUGGCCCUGAUGCAGCGUGGCCAGCCCGCUCUCCUCUACCUGGUGCCCUGCACGCUGGUGACGAGCUGCGCUGUGGCGCUCUGGCGCCGGGAGCUGGGCGUGUUCUGGACGGGCAGCGGCUUUGCGAAAGUCCUACCUCCAUCUCCGUGGGCCCCAGCACCAGCCGACGGCCCGCAGCCUCCCAAAGACUCUGCCACGCCACUCUCCCCGCAGCCGCCCAGCGAAGAACCAGCCACAUCCCCCUGGCCUGCUGAGCAGUCCCCAAAAUCACGCACGUCCGAGGAGAUGGGGGCUGGAGCCCCCAUGCGGGAGCCUGGGAGCCCAGCUGAAUCCGAGGGCCGGGACCAGGCCCAGCCGUCCCCGGUAACCCAGCCUGGCGCCUCGGCCUAGGGGAGGGGUGAGACGCUCGCUGCCGUGCCCGCCACACCAAGAUGUUGGGGCUGCCUGGCGCCCACUGGAGACAGACAGACAGACGCCUGUCCCCCGGGACCGAGGCCUGUGCCGUCCCCACCCGCCCCAACAUGGUGCUCAUCCUUGCCGAGACCCCUGCGGUCUGUGCCCGCGCCCAGCCCAGCUGCCCCGGCUGCACGCCUGCUGCUCCCAGCUCGCCCGGCUGCCACAAGCUCUCUGCGGGUCCAUCCUCCCCACCGGGGUCCGUCCUCGCAGGCCCUGCCCGGCCUCUCUGCAGACCCUCAAGCGUCGUCUGCAUGAGUGAGCAGGCGUGGGUGGACUCUGGCCGCGGCCACACUUGGUGCUCACCAGCUGCUUCGGCCUUCAGGUGACCUCCCUCCCCACGGCAUCCUGCUCUCCGGGUGGAAGAGCAGCUUUCUGUCUCCCAGAAGGCAUCGCUUUUCCCUCUUGAGCAGAUCGGAGCCCCUGGGAGGUUUGGAAGCUGCCUCCAAGCCUAGGACACGGACCAGUGGCCGGGGCGGCCUCUGGCCCCUGACGCUGGCUGAGACAGGCCCGUGGGGCGGGGUUUUGGGGCGUGAACAAGGCUGGCAGUAAGUGGACAAGCUGCUCCCCUGGCUAAGGCCCUGCCCUGCCCUCAGCCAGAGGUGCCUGGCCAUGCCUGCACACUCCUCCCCAUUUUAAUAAAUGGUCGCAACUUCUAGAAGUCCUGCUGGUGCCACCUGGUGGGGUGGACGUCUCUCAGACUGCCCUUCUGACAAGCAGGGGUGGGCGCCAGGCAGGCUGGGUCAGGCCCUCAGGGGUCCCUGGAGCCCUGGGAGGGAGGGACUGGGUCGUGGGAGGUCCUGGUAGCUCCCGGCACCCAACCUCGCUUCCCGUGUGGGCCCCGUGUUGCUUUUCUGCUGAGAGGGGCUUGGGCCUCGGUUCUCCCUGUGGCAGCGGCAUUGGUGCCUGGGUUCUUAACCCUCUGGACCCAGCAGCUAGGAGCUUCUGGAACCCACGAGGACAUCUGCCACUGGCAUGGUCUACUCACUGAUGGGGUCCUCCUGACUCCAGGGCAGAGACGUCCGUGCGGGAACUGACCGAGGCGUGGCCCCAGGCCCCGGCAUCCUCCCCUCGCUGCACGUGGUCACUUCCGAAGCAGCGCUCCCUGUGGCCGCAGAGACAGAGCCCGCACCCUGGCUGUCUGUGGUGCCUGGGCCCCAGCUCCCGCCCGCCACCCGCCCUGUUGAGUGCGGCCUCCAGACUCGAGUCCAGAAUCUGUUUCUGUCAAGUCAGUCGUCCCCAGCUGCACACGGGGACUGCUGAGCGCUGCGCUCUCACGGGUCUGUUCCGGACAGAGGGUGGCAGGGGUGAGCCCUGAUCCCUUACAAAAAAUACCAGCUUCCCAGGGAGUAAUGGCGCCUUCACUGAAGCCAUUUUGUACAUGGGGACGGGGUGGGGACGUCUCUUUUUUGGUGUUGGACGUUUGACCAGUGGGGAGGGGUUCAGAGGCGGCGGUCCUGUCCUUGGCUCCGUCUGUCCGUGUGGCCUUGCUGCCAUUCCGUCUGAUCAUUAAACACAGCUUUUGAUACAUAUGGCCCGGCCUCUGCCUCCGCAGUGCACGGCUUGGGGCAUCUGCUCUGUGCAGGUCCCGGUGAGCAGAACUGAGAGCUGGCAGGCCGCCUGGCUGUCCUGCAGAGGACGGAUUGGAAUUGCCACCGCAGGGCCGGCCAGUGCUGUGAGGUGCCCAGCGUCACUCCCAUGGGCUCUGUGGGCCAUGUGGUCCCUGUCACGCUUCUCAGCUCUGCCACUGUUGCUGGAAAGCAUCACAGACCAUGUGUAAAAUGGGCCAAAAUACCUUUUACAAAAUUAAAAUAGAGAUGGGG